AUGGGACUGGAGGACGAGCAAAAGAUGCUUACCGAAUCCGGAGAUCCUGAGGAGGAGGAAGAGGAAGAGGAGGAAUUAGUGGAUCCCCUAACAACAGUGAGAGAGCAAUGCGAGCAGUUGGAGAAAUGUGUAAAGGCCCGGGAGCGGCUAGAGCUCUAUGAUGAGCAUGUAUCCUCUCGAUCACAUACAGAAGAGGAUUGCACGGAGGAGCUCUUUGACUUCUUGCAUGCAAAGGACCAUUGCGUGGCCCACAAACUCUUUAACAACUUGAAAUAA